GAGACCGCCCAGCGCUGCGGAGCGGGAGGGGAGGCUUCGCGGAACGCUCUCGGCGCCAGGACUCGCGUGCAAAGCCCAGGCCCGGGCGGCCAGACCAAGAGGGAAGAAGCACAGAAUUCCUCAACUCCCAGUGUGCCCAUGAGUAAGAGCAAAUGCUCCGUGGGACUCAUGUCUUCCGUGGUGGCCCCGGCUAAGGAGCCCAAUGCCGUGGGCCCGAAGGAGGUGGAGCUCAUCCUUGUCAAGGAGCAGAACGGAGUGCAGCUCACCAGCUCCACCCUCACCAACCCGCGGCAGAGCCCCGUGGAGGCCCAGGAUCGGGAGACCUGGGGCAAGAAGAUCGACUUUCUCCUGUCCGUCAUUGGCUUUGCUGUGGACCUGGCCAACGUCUGGCGGUUCCCCUACCUGUGCUACAAAAAUGGUGGCGGUGCCUUCCUGGUCCCCUACCUGCUCUUCAUGGUCAUUGCUGGGAUGCCACUUUUCUACAUGGAGCUGGCCCUCGGCCAGUUCAACAGGGAAGGGGCCGCUGGUGUCUGGAAGAUCUGCCCCAUACUGAAAGGUGUGGGCUUCACGGUCAUCCUCAUCUCACUGUAUGUCGGCUUCUUCUACAACGUCAUCAUCGCCUGGGCGCUGCACUAUCUCUUCUCCUCCUUCACCACGGAGCUCCCCUGGAUCCACUGCAACAACUCCUGGAACAGCCCCAACUGCUCGGAUGCCCAUCCUGGUGACUCCAGUGGAGACAGCUCGGGCCUCAACGACACUUUUGGGACCACACCUGCUGCCGAGUACUUUGAACGUGGCGUGCUGCACCUCCACCAGAGCCAUGGCAUCGACGACCUGGGGCCUCCGCGGUGGCAGCUCACAGCCUGCCUGGUGCUGGUCAUCGUGCUGCUCUACUUCAGCCUCUGGAAGGGCGUGAAGACCUCAGGGAAGGUGGUAUGGAUCACAGCCACCAUGCCAUACGUGGUCCUCACUGCCCUGCUCCUGCGUGGGGUCACCCUCCCUGGAGCCAUAGACGGCAUCAGAGCAUACCUGAGCGUUGACUUCUACCGGCUCUGCGAGGCGUCUGUUUGGAUUGACGCGGCCACCCAGGUGUGCUUCUCCCUGGGCGUGGGGUUCGGGGUGCUGAUCGCCUUCUCCAGCUACAACAAGUUCACCAACAACUGCUACAGGGACGCGAUUGUCACCACCUCCAUCAACUCCCUGACGAGCUUCUCCUCCGGCUUCGUCGUCUUCUCCUUCCUGGGGUACAUGGCACAGAAGCACAGUGUGCCCAUCGGGGACGUGGCCAAGGACGGGCCAGGGCUGAUCUUCAUCAUCUACCCGGAAGCCAUCGCCACGCUCCCUCUGUCCUCAGCCUGGGCCGUGGUCUUCUUCAUCAUGCUGCUCACCCUGGGUAUCGACAGCGCCAUGGGUGGUAUGGAGUCAGUGAUCACCGGGCUCAUCGAUGAGUUCCAGCUGCUGCACAGACACCGUGAGCUCUUCACGCUCUUCAUCGUCCUGGCGACCUUCCUCCUGUCCCUGUUCUGCGUCACCAACGGUGGCAUCUACGUCUUCACGCUCCUGGACCAUUUUGCAGCCGGCACGUCCAUCCUCUUUGGAGUGCUCAUCGAAGCCAUCGGAGUGGCCUGGUUCUAUGGUGUUGGGCAGUUCAGCGACGACAUCCAGCAGAUGACCGGGCAGCGGCCCAGCCUGUACUGGCGGCUGUGCUGGAAGCUGGUCAGCCCCUGCUUUCUCCUGUUCGUGGUCGUGGUCAGCAUUGUGACCUUCAGACCCCCCCACUACGGAGCCUACAUCUUCCCCGACUGGGCCAACGCGCUGGGCUGGGUCAUCGCCACAUCCUCCAUGGCCAUGGUGCCCAUCUAUGCGGCCUACAAGUUCUGCAGCCUGCCUGGGUCCUUUCGAGAGAAACUGGCCUACGCCAUUGCACCCGAGAAGGACCGUGAGCUGGUGGACAGAGGGGAGGUGCGCCAGUUCACGCUCCGCCACUGGCUCAAGGUGUAGAGGGAGCAGAGACGAAGACCCCAGGAAGUCAUCCUGCAAUGGGAGAGACACGAACAAACCAAGGAAAUCUAAGUUUCGAGAGAAAGGAGGGCAACUUCUACUCUUCAACCUCUACUGAAAACACAAACAACAAAGCAGAAGACUCCUCUCUUCUGACUGUUUACACCUUUCCGUGCCGGGAGCGCACCUCGCCGUGUCUUGUGUUGCUGUAAUAACGACGUAGAUCUGUGCAGCGAGGUCCACCCCGUUGUUGUCCCUGCAGGGCAGAAAAACGUCUAACUUCAUGCUGUCUGUGUGAGGCUCCCUCCCUCCCUGCUCCCUGCUCCCGGCUCUGAGGCUGCCCCAGGGGCACUGUGUUCUCAGGCGGGGAUCACGAUCCUUGUAGACGCACCUGCUGAGAAUCCCCGUGCUCACAGUAGCUUCCUAGACCAUUUACUUUGCCCAUAUUAAAAAGCCAAGUGUCCUGCUUGGUUUAGCUGUGCAGAAGGUGAAAUGGAGGAAACCACAAAUUCAUGCAAAGUCCUUUCCCGAUGCGUGGCUCCCAGCAGAGGCCGUAAAUUGAGCGUUCAGUUGACACAUUGCACACACAGUCUGUUCAGAGGCAUUGGAGGAUGGGGGUCCUGGUAUGUCUCACCAGGAAAUUCUGUUUAUGUUCUUGCAGCAGAGAGAAAUAAAACUCCUUGAAACCAGCUCAGGCUACUGCCACUCAGGCAGCCUGUGGGUCCUUGCGGUGUAGGGAACGGCCUGAGAGGAGCGUGUCCUAUCCCCGGACGCAUGCAGGGCCCCCACAGGAGCGUGUCCUAUCCCCGGACGCAUGCAGGGCCCCCACAGGAGCAUGUCCUAUCCCUGGACGCAUGCAGGGCCCCCACAGGAGCGUGUACUACCCCAGAACGCAUGCAGGGCCCCCACAGGAGCGUGUACUACCCCAGGACGCAUGCAGGGCCCCCACUGGAGCGUGUACUACCCCAGGACGCAUGCAGGGCCCCCACAGGAGCGUGUCCUAUCCCCGGACCGGACGCAUGCAGGGCCCCCACAGGAGCGUGUACUACCCCAGGACGCAUGCAGGGCCCCCACAGGAGCGUGUACUACCCCAGGAUGCAUGCAGGGCCCCCACAGGAGCGUGUACUACCCCAGGACGCAUGCAGGGCCCCCAUGCAGGCAGCCUGCAGACCACACUCUGCCUGGCCUUGAGCCGUGACCUCCAGGAAGGGACCCCACUGGAAUUUUAUUUCUCUCAGGUGCGUGCCACAUCAAUAACAACAGUUUUUAUGUUUGCGAAUGGCUUUUUAAAAUCAUAUUUACCUGUGAAUCAAAACAAAUUCAAGAAUGCAGUAUCCGCGAGCCUGCUUGCUGAUAUUGCAGUUUUUGUUUACAAGAAUAAUUAGCAAUACUGAGUGAAGGAUGUUGGCCAAAAGCUGCUUUCCAUGGCACACUGCCCUCUGCCACUGACAGGAAAGUGGAUGCCAUAGUUUGAAUUCAUGCCUCAAGUCGGUGGGCCUGCCUACGUGCUGCCCGAGGGCAGGGGCCGUGCAGGGCCAGUCAUGGCUGUCCCCUGCAAGUGGACGUGGGCUCCAGGGACUGGAGUGUAAUGCUCGGUGGGAGCCGUCAGCCUGUGAACUGCCAGGCAGCUGCAGUUAGCACAGAGGAUGGCUUCCCCAUUGCCUUCUGGGGAGGGACACAGAGGACGGCUUCCCCAUCGCCUUCUGGCCGCUGCAGUCAGCACAGAGAGCGGCUUCCCCAUUGCCUUCUGGGGAGGGACACAGAGGACAGCUUCCCCAUCGCCUUCUGGCUGCUGCAGUCAGCACAGAGAGCGGCUUCCCCAUCGCCUUCUGGGGAGGGGCUCCGUGUAGCAACCCAGGUGUUGUCCGUGUCUGUUGACCAAUCUCUAUUCAGCAUCGUGUGGGUCCCUAAGCACAAUAAAAGACAUCCACAAUGGAAAAA